AGUCUCGAGCUCUCGCUGGCCUUCGGGUGUACGUGCUCCGGGAUCUUCAGCACCCGCGGCCGCCAUCGCCGUCGCUUGGCUUCUUCUGGACUCAUCUGCGCCACUUGUCCGCUUCACACUCCGCCGCCAUCAUGGUGAAGCUCGCGAAGGCAGGUAAAAAUCAAGGUGACCCCAAGAAAAUGGCUCCUCCUCCAAAGGAGGUAGAAGAAGAUAGUGAAGAUGAGGAAAUGUCAGAAGAUGAAGAAGAUGAUAGCAGUGGAGAAGAGGUCGUCAUACCUCAGAAGAAAGGCAAGAAGGCUGCUGCAACCUCAGCAAAGAAGGUGGUCGUUUCCCCAACAAAAAAGGUUGCAGUUGCCACACCAGCCAAGAAAGCAGCUGUCACUCCAGGCAAAAAGGCAGCAGCAACACCUGCCAAGAAGACAGUUACACCAGCCAAAGCAGUUACCACACCUGGCAAGAAGGGAGCCACACCAGGCAAAGCAUUGGUAGCAACUCCUGGUAAGAAGGGUGCUGCCAUCCCAGCCAAGGGGGCAAAGAAUGGCAAGAAUGCCAAGAAGGAAGACAGUGAUGAAGAGGAGGAUGAUGACAGUGAGGAGGAUGAGGAGGAUGACGAGGACGAGGAUGAGGAUGAAGAUGAAAUUGAACCAGCAGCGAUGAAAGCAGCAGCUGCUGCCCCUGCCUCAGAGGAUGAGGACGAUGAGGAUGACGAAGAUGAUGAGGAUGACGAUGACGAUGAGGAAGAUGACUCUGAAGAAGAAGCUAUGGAGACUACACCAGCCAAAGGAAAGAAAGCUGCAAAAGUUGUUCCUGUGAAAGCCAAGAACGUGGCUGAGGAUGAAGAUGAAGAAGAGGAUGAUGAGGACGAGGAUGACGACGACGACGAAGAUGAUGAAGAUGAUGAUGAUGAAGAUGAUGAGGAGGAGGAAGAAGAGGAGGAGGAAGAGCCUGUCAAAGAAGCACCUGGAAAACGAAAGAAGGAAAUGGCCAAACAGAAAGCAGCUCCUGAAGCCAAGAAACAGAAAGUGGAAGGCACAGAACCGACUACGGCUUUCAAUCUCUUUGUUGGAAACCUAAACUUUAACAAAUCUGCUCCUGAAUUAAAAACUGGUAUCAGCGAUGUUUUUGCUAAAAAUGAUCUUGCUGUUGUGGAUGUCAGAAUUGGUAUGACUAGGAAAUUUGGUUAUGUGGAUUUUGAAUCUGCUGAAGACCUGGAGAAAGCGUUGGAACUCACUGGUUUGAAAGUCUUUGGCAAUGAAAUUAAACUAGAGAAACCAAAAGGAAAAGACAGUAAGAAAGAGCGAGAUGCGAGAACACUUUUGGCUAAAAAUCUCCCUUACAAAGUCACUCAGGAUGAAUUGAAAGAAGUGUUUGAAGAUGCUGCGGAGAUCAGAUUAGUCAGCAAGGAUGGGAAAAGUAAAGGGAUUGCUUAUAUUGAAUUUAAGACAGAAGCUGAUGCAGAGAAAACCUUUGAAGAAAAGCAGGGAACAGAGAUCGAUGGGCGAUCUAUUUCCCUGUACUAUACUGGAGAGAAAGGUCAAAAUCAAGACUAUAGAGGUGGAAAGAAUAGCACUUGGAGUGGUGAAUCAAAAACUCUGGUUUUAAGCAACCUCUCCUACAGUGCAACAGAAGAAACUCUUCAGGAAGUAUUUGAGAAAGCAACUUUUAUCAAAGUACCCCAGAACCAAAAUGGCAAAUCUAAAGGGUAUGCAUUUAUAGAGUUUGCUUCAUUCGAAGACGCUAAAGAAGCUUUAAAUUCCUGUAAUAAAAGGGAAAUUGAGGGCAGAGCAAUCAGGCUGGAGUUGCAAGGACCCAGGGGAUCACCUAAUGCCAGAAGCCAGCCAUCCAAAACUCUGUUUGUCAAAGGCCUGUCUGAGGAUACCACUGAAGAGACAUUAAAGGAGUCAUUUGACGGCUCCGUUCGGGCAAGGAUAGUUACUGACCGGGAAACUGGGUCCUCCAAAGGGUUUGGUUUUGUAGACUUCAACAGUGAGGAGGAUGCCAAAGCUGCCAAGGAGGCCAUGGAAGACGGUGAAAUUGAUGGAAAUAAAGUUACCUUGGACUGGGCCAAACCUAAGGGUGAAGGUGGCUUCGGGGGUCGUGGUGGAGGCAGAGGCGGCUUUGGAGGACGAGGUGGUGGUAGAGGAGGCCGAGGAGGAUUUGGUGGCAGAGGCCGGGGAGGCUUUGGAGGGCGAGGAGGCUUCCGAGGAGGCAGAGGAGGAGGAGGUGACCACAAGCCACAAGGAAAGAAGACGAAGUUUGAAUAGCUUCUGUCCCUCUGCUUUCCCUUUUCCAUUUGAAAGAAAGGACUCUGGGGUUUUUACUGUUACCUGAUCAAUGACAGAGCCUUCUGAGGACAUUCCAAGACAGUAUACAGUCCUGUGGUCUCCUUGGAAAUCCGUCUAGUUAACAUUUCAAGGGCAAUACCGUGUUGGUUUUGACUGGAUAUUCAUAUAAACUUUUUAAAGAGUUGAGUGAUAGAGCUAACCCUUAUCUGUAAGUUUUGAAUUUAUAUUGUUUCAUCCCAUGUACAAAACCAUUUUUUCCUACAAAUAGUUUGGGUUUUGUUGUUGUUUCUUUUUUUUGUUUUGUUUUUGUUUUUUUUUUUUUUGCGUUCGUGGGGUUGUAAAAGAAAAGAAAGCAGAAUGUUUUAUCAUGGUUUUUGCUUCAGCGGCUUUAGGACAAAUUAAAAGUCAACUCUGGUGCCAGACGUGUUACUUCCUAAAGAGUGUUUCCCCUGGAAUGUCACUGGAGAGCAUGGCAAAGCCAGCUCUGCCACUUGCUUCACCCAUCCCAAUGGAAAUGGCUUAGUGCGUGUUUCCAGUAUCCCAGCCCUAACUAACUUGGUUGAAAUGCUGGUGAGGGGACCUGCUCCUGCAGCCCUGGUGCUGACUUGAAGGCUGCUGCAGCUUCUCCUACUUUUAGCAGGUCUGAGGAUUAUGUCCUGAAGACCACUCUGGAAAGAGGUGCAGGAACAGAUUAGUCAGGUUUCCUAGGACAAGGAAGAGCUUCAGGGAAGAGCAGUGGCUAACUCCUGUAAUCCCAACACUUGGGGAGGCCGAGGCAGGCAGAUCAACUGAGGUCAGGAGUUGAAGACCAGCCUGGCCAACAUGGUGAAAGCCCAUCUCUACUAAAAAUACAAAAAUUAGCUGGGCAUGGUGGUGUACUCCUGUAGUCCCAGCUACUCAGGAGGCUGAAGCGGGAGAGUCACGUGAACCCGGGAAGCAGAGUGAGCUGAGCACACACUACUAUACUCCAGGCUGGGUAACAAAGCGAGACUCCCAUCUCCCAAAAAGCAGUUCUGGAAUAGAACUCACGCUAGAUGGAUAGACCAGUGGACACUUUGGAACCUUGGGGCUGGGGAGGAAACUGCCCAUCCAGUAAACCCCCAAAAAGCCAUUUGUUCUGCACUACGUAUAUUGCUUAUUCUUUCUGGUCUUAAGUACUUGCCUCUCAACCUCCCUUUUUAGUAAAAGACAAGGCCACGUGAGAGGCGGGACUAUCAACAUUGUGAUGAAUUUACUUGAAACCCAGUGCCCAAAAUCAAUGUAGGUAGCCAAGUCCAAAAACCUGUUCUAGUCCAACUAGUGAAAUCAAACUGUGAUACUUGGAUAAGCUUAGAAGGAAACGUGAAGAAUACGUAGCUGCUUUGGGUUUACUCUGGUUCAGUUGGGCUGUUGAAAUCUUAACAUCCUUGGGCUUAUCACCUACUGCUUGUCAGCCCUGUUCCAUGUCCAGGGGAUGGGGGUGGUGACAAUCCAGUUCCAAGACCCUCAUGCUCUAGAGAGGAAGGUGGCCAGCCAGGGUUGUAACUACGAUGAAAAAGCAGUGGGAGGGUCUCCUAUGAGGCAAGCCUAAGGACAAAAAGGAAGGCCUUGCAGCCUGUAUUCUGGAUAAGGAAUUAAAAGCUCAGUUAAUUGAAGCCCA